AAGGUAUCAUGAACAACAAGUCAUCAACAGUAGGCAACAGAAACAAAAUUGCAAACAUUUUGGAUGCAGACUAUUGGGAAGUCUGUAAUACAAUUAUCCUUAGGAAAGGCAAUAAAGAAAAUAUCUUUGACAACGGGACCUAUGUAAAAUGCUCUCCUUUGAACCUUCUAGAUUGAAAAAACAACCAAAUAGUUCUAGAUAUAAAAGCACACAGUAAUGGAAACGGAACAGCUACAUGCACGUCACAGUAGGUUACAGUGCGGAGCGACACCUGCGAGGACUUCUGUGAGCUCCCAGUGAGCUUCAGACAUUCUGUCUGCAGCUCCAAAGAUGGGUUAAUUUGCCCGAUACACAGCAGAACUCUCCUGUUCCUGUAAUUCGAGUGGCCUCCAAAAAGAGGUUGUCGUUGACUCUUUUAGGUGCGUGCAGUGUGGGUAUGUUUUUUCUCUUUCUGAAAGGAGGACAUUUCAGCGGACGGCAGAGAAUACAGAUUUAUGCCAGCGCCCUGCGGAAGGAGCCUCUGGCGGGUCAUCUCCAUUUAUGGGAGAUCGCAGAGCGGUGAGCAAAGUCUUGCACCAGCGGGGAUGUCGGGGUGGAACUGAACCUGUUGUAGGGGACCCCCAGUGUGCCCUGGUUUCUGGGGCUGAUUCAUUACGUCACUUAGUUUCUACUAUUCUCAUGCCACCCCGCCAAUUACUAGACAUAAAACGUUCCCAGGGAAGCCCGGCUAGCUCAGUCGGUAGAGCAUGGGACUCUUAAUCUCAGGGUCGUGGGUUCGAGCCCCACGUUGGGCGACUUGUUUUCUUCCUUGCUACCUUGGAGUUCUGGAAACAGCCAGCAUUUAAUGAACACUACCAGGAUCCCAGGCCCAUGAGCGGGACAAACCAGUCGAGUGUCUCCGAGUUCCUCCUCCUGGGACUCUCCAGGCAGCCCCAGCAGCAGCAUCUCCUCUUUGUGUUCUUCCUCAGCAUGUACCUGGCCACUGUCCUGGGGAACCUGCUCAUCAUCCUGUCCGUAAGCAUAGACUCCUGCCUGCACACCCCCAUGUACUUCUUCCUCAGCAACCUGUCUUUUGUGGACAUCUGCUUCUCCUUCACCACCGUCCCCAAGAUGCUGGCCAAUCACAUACUCGAGACUCAGACCAUCUCCUUCUGUGGCUGUCUCACACAGAUGUAUUUCGUUUUCAUGUUCGUGGACAUGGACAAUUUCCUCCUAGCUGUGAUGGCCUAUGACCACUUUGUCGCCGUGUGCCACCCCUUACAUUACACAGCAAAGAUGACCCAUCAGCUCUGUGCCCUGCUGGUUGCUGGAUUAUGGGUGGUUGCCAACCUGAAUGUCCUUCUGCACACCCUGCUGAUGGCUCCACUCUCAUUCUGUGCAGACAAUGCCAUCACUCACUUCUUCUGCGAUGUGACUCCCCUACUGAAACUCUCCUGCUCAGACACACACCUCAAUGAGGUCAUAAUCCUUAGUGAGGGUGCCCUGGUCAUGAUCACCCCAUUUCUUUGCAUCCUGGCUUCUUAUAUGCACAUCACCUGCACUGUCCUGAAGGUCCCAUCCACAAAGGGAAGGUGGAAAGCCUUCUCCACCUGUGGUUCUCACCUGGCUGUGGUUCUCCUCUUCUACAGCACCAUCAUUGCUGUGUAUUUUAACCCUCUGUCCUCCCACUCAGCUGAGAAAGACACUAUGGCUACUGUGUUGUAUACAGUAGUGACUCCCAUGCUAAACCCUUUCAUCUACAGCCUGAGGAACAGGUACUUGAAAGGGGCUCUGAAAAAAGUAGUUGGCAGGGUGGUGUUUUCUGUCUGAUGAAAUAAUCAAGACUGAAUCUCAUUCCCAAGGAAAUUUAUUUUUCACCAAUUGAGUUUAAUGCAGUAGUUGUUUCAUUAAAUGAUGUUCUUGCUAGUGACACACUUAGUAAUUAUACUAAGUUAAACUAUUAAUUAUAAUUUUUUUUGAGACAGGGUCAUGCUCUGUCACCCAGGCUGGAGUGCAGUGCCGUGAUCUUGGCUCACUGCACCCUCCAUCUCCCAGGCUCAAGUGAUCCUCCUGCCUCAGCCUCCUGAGUAGCUGGGACCACAGGUGUGUGCCACAUGCCUAGCUAAAUUUUUUUUUUUUUUUUUGAGACGGAGUCUCUCUAUGUCGCCAGGCUGGAUGCUGUUGCGGGAAGUCAGGGACCCUGAACAGAGGGACCAGCUGGAGCUGUGUCAGAGGAACAUAAAUUGUGAAGAUUUCAUUUUAAUAUGGACAUGUAUCGGUUCCCAAAAUUAAUACUUUUAUAAUUUCUUACGCCUGUCUUUACUGCAAUCUCUGAACAUAAGCUGUGAAGAUUUCACGGACAUUUAUCAGUUCCCGAAAUUAACACUUAUAAUUUCUCAUGCCUGUCUUUACUUUAAUCUCUUAAUCCUGUUAUCUUCGUAAGCUGACGAUGUACGUCACCUCAGGACCACUGUGAUAAUUCUACCUAACUAUACAAAUUGAUUGUAAAACAUGUGUAUUUGAACAAUAUGAAAUCAGUGCACCUUGAAAAAGAACAGAAUAACAGUGAUUUUAGGGAACAAGGGAAGAUAAUCAUAAGGUCUGACUAUCUGUGGAGUUGGGCAGAAUGGAGCCAUAUUUUUCUUCUUGCAGAGAGCCUAUAAAUGGACGUGCAAGUAGGGAUAUCACUGAAUUCUUUUCCUAGCAAGGAAUGUUAAUAAUUAAGACCUUGGGAGAGGAAUGCACUCCUCGGGGGAGGUCUAUAAAUGGCUGCUCUGGGAGAGUCUGUCUUAUGCAGUUGAGAUAAGGACUGAAAUAUGCCCUGGUCUCCUGCAGUACCCUCAGGCUUAUUAGUGUGGGGAAAAAACCCCACCCUGGUGAAUUUAAGGUCAGACAGAUUCUCUGCUCUUGAACCCUGUUUUCUGUUGUUUAAGAUGUUUAUCAAGACAAUACGUGCACAGCUGAACAUAGACCCUUAUCUGGAGGUUUUGAUUUUGUCCUUUGCCUUGUGAUCUCUAUUGGCUUCAGAGGCAUGUGAUCUUUGUUCUCCUUUUUGCCCUUUGACACCUGUGAUCUCUGUGACCUACUCCCUGUUCGUACACCCCCACCCCUUUUAAAGUCCUUAAUAAAAACCUCCUGGUUUUGCGGCUCA